AAACUCUUUCUUCGGCUCGCGAGCUGAGAGGAGCAGGUAGAGGGGCAGAGGCGGGACUGUCGUCUGGGGGUGAGUGUCGGCAGCCCCCGGAGGAUCUGGCGGACCCCAGUGGUGGGGGUUUGGGGGUGGGGAAGUUGUGGCUCUGGAGAAGCCCCUGCCGGUCUCCACCGCGCAUACCCUGCAGAUGUGGGAACAUUCGGGAGCCCCGAGUCUCGAGAACCCGGUUGCCCUCACCCAUCCGUAAUUGUCUCCGGCGUUCCCAAGGCCAGCUCGGACCUGGGUCGGGGAGGAAGCCUCCCCCACAGCUGGCGACCCGGGACCCCGGCGCCCCUCCCAGAUUGGGCGGGAUCAGACCCCCGAGGCGGAUGCCGCUUAGUCAGACUUGGCUGUUACUGUUACCUGUGUUGUUGAGAUUAUUGGCCCCUUGGUUGGGAGUAUCUGGGCAAGCCAGCGCUGGGGUCCCCGGUUGGGUUUGGGAACUGCAGGUGACCCCCAGUCUCUCCCUGCGGUUCCGGUGCUGCAGGCCCUGCCAGGUGGCUGGGCGGCAUUCCAGGGGCCCUGGCUGCGUGGCAUGGACACAUUGCUGAACCGGCCUCAGUUUCCCCUCCGUGAGGUGGAACAAUGAACCAGCUGGGAUGAGGAUGCCCGAAGCGUUUAGUCAAAGGAAAUUUUUGUGAUGAGGUGUACUGCUGGCCACUGGGGGCCCUUGCGUGACUGGCGUUAGGUCUCUGAGCCUCAGUUUCCCUGUGUGUUAAGGGGGGGUCUCAUGGCAUGGGACCUUGGCGAGGAUGAGUUGAGUGGAUAGGAGCUGUGGCCACUCAGUGGGUGCCCAGGGACAGUCAGCUGUCAUCAUAAUUAUAUUAAUUAUGUCUGUAGCCACUGUUCAGAUUCACUCCUGUUCCAAGAAUCCCGACCAUCUUUUCCUCUGGGUCAGAUUUAAACUUUUUGUUUGUUUGUUUUAUUUGUAGAGGUGGGGGACUCACUUUGUCACCCAGGCUGGAGUACAGUGGCUCCAUGCACUGUAUUCACUGCAGCCUCAACCUCCUGGGCUCAAGUGAUCCUCCCACCUCAGCCUCCCGAGUAGCUGGGACUACAGGUGCACACCACAGGCAGCUAAUUUUAAAAUUUUUUUGUGUGUGGAGACGGGGUCUCACUAUGUUGUCCAGGCUGGUCUCAAACUCCUGGGCCCAAGCAAUCCUCCUGCCUUGGCAUCUGAAAGUGCUGGGAUUUCAGGCAUGAGCCACUAUGCCCAGCUCUGAUUUUUUUAAAUGGACACUUCUCAAGAGGAAACUGAGGUCGCCCCUCAACUUGGGCGGGGGACUCCUGCAGUCCAGAUCUGGGAUUCAGGGCCCAUGGGAAGCCACCUGGCCGUCUAGGUCUGGGGCCAGCCCUGGGGGCCAUCACUUCCUCCCACUGGCCUGUUCUCAAGGUGACACCAGGCAGGGCUGGUGUCAGGAGGAAGAGGUGUGGCCCCCAGGUCAGGCAGCUGGGCCCCCAUAUGGCCUAGGUGAGCAGUUGGGUGUUUGCUCAGUCCAGCCUGGACACCCUCCCUCACUCUCACCCCUAGGGUGUGGCAUUUCCUGGCAGGUGCUCUGGGUGUGGGAGAACCAAAAGGGGGCCUUGGUGCUUCUCUGUUCCAGGCCAGAGUUCAGGAAUCCAGACAAGCCAGGUCAGCCCAGGAGGAGCAAGUAAGGGCUCACUGAGUGACAUUUCCUCCUGCCACCAGCCUCUGAGGCCCAGAGCAAGCAGGAAUUUGCUCACUCCCCCAACCCCAUGAGCCAGGGAGGAUGCCUAUUGUGGACCCUCUUCCUGGUGGGAAUCUGGCUUGCCUUGAUUGCUCCUCAUGAUGGUGAGGUCACUACCAACGUGGCAAACUAAAGGAAAUCUCAUCAGCUGGGAGUUAAAGACAGGAACUAGGCUCCCACCCAACCUUUCUUAGGUGGAUUUCUAGGCCUCUCUGUGCCUCAAUUUUCCUAUCCAUAAAAAUGGAGCUAAUGCAGCCCUACUUCUCAGCACACAUAUAGAGUUUAGAUGGACAGAUGGUGGCCAGGCUGCACACAGGACCUGGCAUAUUGAUCCUAGUCCUAAUUAUGCAGCUCAUUAUGUUAUCAUUUAUAGCAUGUAUCUUUGCACACAGAAAUAAUAUCAUGAAUAUUUCUGAGCUCUAAGUACAAGACUUGGAGAAGAGCUCUGACCAGCCUGAAGGUGUGGGGGUCCAGGAAGUCCCCAGAGGAGGGGCCCAGGAGACCUCAGUUCCCCCAUCACUCCUGGAUUGUGGGAAGGGUCUGAGGUUGAACUGCGAUGCACGGCCUGGCUUCCCAGCCUGUUUCCCCAUCUAUGGAGUGAGCCCAAAGAUGCCCUUUGAGACUCCACUGGGCCAGGGCUGGUGUUAUUCAGGGGCCCCUUUCCAGUCUCACAUAGGUGCCCCAGGCAGUUCCUGCAAUGGGGUAGGGCUGGCAUGGAUGACAUACAAUUAGUCAUCCAUGACAGAGCCUCGGGACCUAGAAACCCGGGACACCAAAGUCUAAAGUGCAUGUGUCACCGUGCCCAACCCCACCCCUUUUUCCAUACCCAGGCACUCCCUGGUGCAGAUAUUGAGUAUAUAUUGACAGAGAACUCACUAGUACACAUGGUUUCACUAAAGCAGGGUCCGGCCAUUGUGAACUUAAAGGAUUUACUGGGCUAUUUCUUCUUCUUUUCUUCCCCUUCUGUUUGCAAAAGCAACUCCUGCUCCUUGUAAAAAGGGACCAGCCUAUCAUUACUGGGAAACCCAAACUGGAGCCGCCCAGGAGGCUCCUCAGGCCGACCCCAGACCCUGGCUGGCCAGGAUGAAGUAUCUCCGGCACCGGCGGCCCAAUGCCACCCUCAUUCUGGCCAUCGGCGCUUUCACCCUCCUCCUCUUCAGUCUGCUAGUGUCACCACCCACCUGCAAGGUCCAGGAGCAGCCACCGGCGAUCCCCGAGGCCCUGGCCUGGCCCACUCCACCCACCCGCCCAGCCCCGGCCCCGUGCCAUGCCAACACCUCUAUGGUCACCCACCCGGACUUCGCCACGCAGCCGCAGCACGUUCAGAACUUCCUCCUGUACAGACACUGCCGCCACUUUCCCCUGCUGCAGGACGUGCCCCCCUCUAAGUGCGCGCAGCCGGUCUUCCUGCUGCUGGUGAUCAAGUCCUCCCCUAGCAACUAUGUGCGCCGCGAGCUGCUGCGGCGCACGUGGGGCCGCGAGCGCAAGGUACGGGGUUUGCAGCUGCGCCUCCUCUUCCUGGUGGGCACAGCCUCCAACCCGCACGAGGCCCGCAAGGUCAACCGGCUGCUGGAGCUGGAGGCACAGACUCACGGAGACAUCCUGCAGUGGGACUUCCACGACUCCUUCUUCAACCUCACGCUCAAGCAGGUCCUGUUCUUACAGUGGCAGGAGACAAGGUGCGCCAACGCCAGCUUCGUGCUCAACGGGGAUGAUGACGUCUUUGCACACACAGACAACAUGGUCUUCUACCUGCAGGACCAUGACCCUGGCCGCCACCUCUUCGUGGGGCAACUGAUCCAAAACGUGGGCCCCAUCCGGGCUUUUUGGAGCAAGUACUAUGUGCCAGAGGUGGUGACUCAGAAUGAGCGGUACCCACCCUAUUGUGGGGGUGGUGGCUUCUUGCUGUCCCGCUUCACGGCCGCUGCCCUGCGCCGUGCUGCCCAUGUCUUGGACAUCUUCCCCAUUGAUGAUGUCUUCCUGGGUAUGUGUCUGGAGCUUGAGGGACUGAAGCCUGCCUCCCACAGCGGCAUCCGCACGUCUGGCGUGCGGGCUCCAUCGCAACGCCUGUCCUCCUUUGACCCCUGCUUCUACCGAGACCUGCUGCUGGUGCACCGCUUCCUACCUUAUGAGAUGCUGCUCAUGUGGGAUGCGCUGAACCAGCCCAACCUCACCUGCGGCAAUCAGACACAGAUCUACUGAGUCAGCAUCAGGGUCCCCAGCCUCUGGGCUCCUGUUUCCAUAGGAAGGGGCGACACCUUCCUCCCAGGAAGCUGAGACCUUUGUGGUCUGAGCAUAAGGGAGUGCCAGGGAAGGUUUGAGGUUUGAUGAGUGAAUAUUCUGGCUGGCGAACUCCUACACAUCCUUCAAAACCCACCUGGUACUGUUCCAGCAUCUUCCCUGGAUGGCUGGAGGAACUCCAGAAAAUAUCCAUCUUCUUUUUGUGGCUGCUAAUGGCAGAAGUGCCUGUGCUAGAGUUCCAACUGUGGAUGCAUCCGUCCCGUUUGAGUCAAAGUCUUACUUCCCUGCUCUCACCUACUCACAGACGGGAUGCUAAGCAGUGCACCUGCAGUGGUUUAAUGGCAGAUAAGCUCCGUCUGCAGUUCCAGGCCAGCCAGAAACUCCUGUGUCCACAUAGAGCUGACGUGAGAAAUAUCUUUCAGCCCAGGAGAGAGGGGUCCUGAUCUUAACCCUUUCCUGGGUCUCAGACAACUCAGAAGGUUGGGGGGAUACCAGAGAGGUGGUGGAAUAGGACCGCCCCCUCCUUACUUGUGGGAUCAAAUGCUGUAAUGGUGGAGGUGUGGGCAGAGGAGGGAGGCAAGUGUCCUUUGAAAGUUGUGAGAGCUCAGAGUUUCUGGGGUCCUCAUUAGGAGCCCCCAUCCCUGUGUUCCCCAAGAAUUCAGAGAACAGCACUGGGGCUGGAAUGAUCUUUAAUGGGCCCAAGGCCAACAGGCAUAUGCCUCACUACUGCCUGGAGAAGGGAGAGAUUCAGGUCCUCCAGCAGCCUCCCUCACCCAGUAUGUUUUACAGAUUACGGGGGGACCGGGUGAGCCAGUGACCCCCUGUAGCCCCCAGCUUCAGGCCUCAGUGUCUGCCAGUCAAGCUUCACAGGCAUUGUGAUGGGGCAGCCUUGGGGAAUAUAAAAUUUUGUGAAGACUUGGAGAUCUUUUUUUUUUUUUAAGCAAAUUUACAAGUUUCAACAGACAAGUCCACAUUCAUCCCUAAAAGUCUCAUUUUCCAGUAGAAAAUAUACACUGGUAAAAACGGGGCAUGGGGCCGUGGCUCAGGGCUGUAAUUCUAGCACAUUGGGAGACCAAAGUGGGAGGAUCACUUGAGCCCAGGAGUUCUGGAUCCUGUCUCUGCACAAAAUAAAAAAUUACUCAGGCGUGGUGGUGCUCACAUGCCUGUAGUCCCAGCUAUACUUGGGAGGCUGAGGCGAGAGGAUCGCUUGAGCCCAGGAGUUGGAGGCUGCAGUGAACCAUGAUUGCGCCACUGUACUCCACUGGGCGGCAAUAAGAAGACAAAAACAUAAAACAGGACAUGUGUGAGGCAAAAGCUGCAGGAAUUUCUAUCAGGCAGAUCUGACCUCAUCCCACCCACCCCCUGCUCAGAUACCCUUCAUAGCUCCUUAUUGCUUUCAGCUCAUAACCCCACAU